AGGAUGUUCUUUGCUCCUUCAGCAAAUUGUAGAUCGGCGGCGAAGCCUGGGAGUCCUGUGGAAAGCAGACGCCCCCACCCACCGCACCCCACCCCCCACUGCCCUUCCCUCGCCACUGCUGUCUCAGCUUGUGCUAAAUUACCCUUCCGGGCGAGAAUUAUACUCCACCCCUGUUCGUAGGAUGACUGGUCUGGAUUUGGGGAUGGGACUUUCCGAGAGAAGGUGGUGUCCCAGCUGGCUUGCCCAAAAUUCACUCUAGGUUUUCAGCUGGUCAGAGAGCAAAGCAGUCGUCCCCCCGAACACUCUGCCUCGUUUCCACACCCGCCACUGCCCAUUUCCUACCCAGAUUGGAAAAAAAGAAAGAAAAAAGCAAAAUGAAGAGCAAGUGAUCAUGCAGCCCAUUUUUUUUUAAGGUGGGGUGGCAGUGAUUUUGCAGUGGUCUCCAAAUAACUGUUACAGUGAUGGUAAUUGUGAAGUACACAAUUUCCUAAACAGGAAGAAAACAAACAAACAAACCGGUUUCUCAAACUUUCCUUAAGAUGAAAAUCUGAUUGCUUCAAAAGAGUCAACUUCACCAGGAGUCAAAUCCGCUCCCACACGAAGUGAGGCAUUUAUGCAUAUUUAUUUACCCGGAAGCCAUUUAAGGACAUCUGGAUCAGCCUCGGUUGUUCUUGGAGGGUUCGGGAAGGGAGAAUGUAAAAACAAGUGCUCCUCUCCGGAUGGGCACUGGUACACGCGGUCAUCUCACUCCUGAGUUCGGUCUCUGGGUACACAUGGUAUUUAGCAGCUGGUUUUCAUCCUUAUGACAUAAGUAAAAACAAUAUUUCCCAACACCUUCCAAUAACUCUUUCUUAUAUGGCAGAAGUACUGAAGACUAUGCAAUUUUUGGUUUCUCUGGUUUCAUUAAAAACCUUUUAAUUGUGGCUUUCGGAGUUGGCCCCAGGUGUUGGACUCUUUUCAUUACAUUUUGCUCUAAUGUGAUGAAAUUCUAAUUCUCUCCUUACCAUAUGGUUAAAUUUCCCCACUGAGAAUUAGUUGAAAAAGGAGAAAUAAUCUAUUAAUCUCUGUAAUAGAUUCACAAAUGAGGUUCGCCACAGAACCUGUUUUUGAAUGGUAAUAUCAGAACAGUUGGGCACCUUAUUUCAUAAAGGAAGGGUGAGGGCGACACAAAAAUGUCUGUAUUUUCACCUGGAAAGGAUGAAAGGGGCUCAGCAGUAUCUUCCAUAAUAAUUCCCUGAGAUCCAGUCUUCCGGGGACAGAAAUACUACGUAGACGUCGGUUACCUACGCUCCUUUGGAUGUCCUGGAACCUAAAGACUGAGAAAGAUCAGGCGGGGCUACGGGAGGCUCUUGUGCCUGGGACCGAGACCGGGGGUUCUGCAGGCUUGAGCGGUCCCACUUGUCUCGUCUGGGACCCCGAGGCUGUUUACAUGCAGGGCAGCCCCUCGCUCACCGCACCCCUCCCACCGUCCCUCCCCCGGCGUUCGCAGCUGUUAACCUCUCCCUUUAGAAAGCUAAAGACACGCUAGUGUUAUUGUUUUUCAAUUAGCAGCUUUGUUUUCACUGGGAUCAUAAACAAAGGUUCUCUCUAAACAUAGGUGGGUCGUGUAUGCAUGACACUAACUUAUCAAAGUCCUUGGGUCACUUUCGGGAGGGCGGAGGCUGGCCCGGUCGUGGCUCUGGGCAGGAUGGGGACACAUCUCACAAUGUCUGACUUAGUUCUCCAGCCAGCUUGCCCUUUUUGUGGGCUGCCACCUUCUGCGGGGCGCCAGGAUUCUUGCCGGCCCGAAGUGGACAUUUGAAGGGCGAAGGAUCGAUCAUGUCAGGGACUGGUGGGGGGUGCCAUGCGGGGCUGUGAGCGGCAGAGCCGGGAUGGCAGAGCAGGGGCGACACUGAGGGCGGCAAAGGCCCUGCCAGCUCAGCUAGACCCAGGAUCUUCGCAGGACCUUUGUCUUUCGCCCUUAGGCAACAAACACUUGAGCGCAUCUCGUGGCCCUUCCCGACCCCAUCUCCACGACCUCCUGCCACCUCCCUCCUCUCCCUGGCCAUCCAAGCUUCUGGAACAAACUUUUGCACAACUUCAUUUUACUCGGGCAAUGAAAACACAUCUGCCCGGUGUCUCGUUACUUGGUUUAAUCGUCGCCAGCCCUAAGUCACGGCCUCGGCUCCCUCUCCUCAACUGUGUGGGAUCCCGCCGCCUGGUUUCGGCCGGGCGGAGGGGUGACGUCAGCCGCUCACACAGUGCCCCCUGGCCGCUGGAGCUCGGGAAAUCUGUGCGCUCGAACUUGGCUCCGCCAAGAAGCUGGGCAAGGAUCCGGGCUCCUGAUGGAACUGGCAAGUUGGAAAAGUGGCAAAGGAAAAGCCAACAUGAGCGCUUUCGGCUUGCGCGGGCAGAAAGGGUGGGAAAUCAGGCCACGGCGAAAUCUUCUGACUCACAGAUGACCGCUUAGAAUGAAAACUACGGAAGGGAAGUCCUCUGACUCUGCAGUUUCACAGAGAGUCACUGAGUUACCAAAGCAGUUGGGAAACAGAGGCAGAGGACUGCCCCCACUCUGUCCGCAGCAGGGGUAUGGGAGGCAGCUCGGGACACUCCAGGGACCAAGCGGGCAGUGGGCGCCGUCCCCGAGGAACACCCAGCCCAGCGCCCCUGGUUCUGGGCUGGUUGGCUUAUCGAGGCCGGUUGGCCAAAGCAUCAGGAAAGGGAACAUUCUCGGCCGGGUGUUGGAUACCAAAUUAUAAACGCCAGAGCACCUUGUGUAAAGAUGAAUAUCGUUUUGUUACUGCGGGAGGGAAUACACCUACUGCUUUGAAAGGAGUUUAAAAUAUUCAGCAGACAGCACCGCAUUGAAAUUAGUGCAUUGAGCUGCAGACCAAACUAAUUUCUAGGUACUAUUUAAAUUUCUUAAUGAUCAUCUUGAUAUUUGCUUGAAAUUUGAGAUAGGAACCCAAGUAAAAUCAGAAUGGAACAUAAUCUACUCUAAAGAGUAAAGCCAGAAGUUCGUCUUUGUUAUUUUUAUAGUACUGAUAAAUAGUUUAUUACUUCACUAGUUUGAAAAGUUACAAGUCUGAAUUUGGGUAGCUAUGUGUAUCUUCUGAGAAGGAAAAUUGUCUCUCUGUGUUUUUCAAUUUAUCUCUUUCAGAACAGUCUAAAAAGUAAAAACAAAGUUUGGCAAAAAUGACAACUUUGCUUGAGAACAGCUCUGGAAAAGCGAAUCCACUGAGAGCCGUGGGAAUUCUCCGCCAGCUGUGCUUCCCCAACCGAGGAAGAAUCCAACCCGGAAUAUCGUUUCUGGACCCCACCGCGGAGACCCCAGCUGGACCCUCUCCUGAAAACUGCCCGGGGAGGGGGGUGCGGUCUCAGCGCCCUCCACUGCGGGGUCCAAGGCGCAGUAGCGGGGCGCGACCCCAGCGCUCCAAGCCCAGCAUUCUUGGCAGCUCUCCAGGCCCCAGUCAGAGGCACAUUGACCUUGAAGUUGCACUUGACUCGCCCACUCGGGGCUGCCUGGUGGCGCCUGGGUCAGCUUGAAACCCACGCAGCUGAGGGAGCUAGGUGUGGGGUUCACCAUACUGCGCCCCCGCCGGAUUUGGGAGCGCGGGAUCUACUCGGAGGCAGAGAGAUUAGCCCCAGAGGUCAAGCCUUUCGGCGUCGUUUUGUCAUCUGUAUUUUCUCGUCCCCUUCGCCGCCGAGUCCUACAAAGCUCACUUCAGAGAGACUGGGUCCACAUGUGUGGGCUCAUGAGGAGGAGGACAGCGAGGGUGACGACGCUGGGGGACUAGCGCGAGCUGGCGCAUUCCUGGCAGUGAGCCAAGGGCCCCCCGUCUUGCUAGUCUUUCCAAGUUGCUUGGCAAUUCCAAAAAUUUCGACUGUGGGAAAGUUGAAACUUGUUCGUAUAGCGUUCUUUCGAAAAGAUUUUCCUUGUCUGUAUCUAUUUUACAGAAAACAUACUGGUCCUCACUACUGUUUGGGGACGAGUUAGCCUAAAUUUGAACAGACCUUGAAGACAAACCCUGAGCCCCGGGAGGCAGCCUUCUCAGCGCGAGGUGCACACACAAGUCCCCGAGCCCACCGCGAGGGUCUCACCUGGCUCCUGCGUGGUCUUUCCCCACUUUGGCGACUUUGAAGGCCAGGGGGACCGUACAGUGAGCGAAUAACUUAGCGCCUGCAUUAUCACUGCUGAAACCUCAGAGAACAAUGUAGGACAUGCGGGUGCAGGUAGAGCAAAACUAGUGAAAAGAGUUUAUGAGGAAUUCAUACCGCCUCGCCUACUUGGGACAACUCCUUCAUUCAGUUGUCCUCCCUAGGGGGCUGUUAUGCUUAUUUGUGUCAGACCCUUCUUUCCCCUGGAAUCUUAUCAUCACAGAAUAUUAAACAUUUGAAAAAAUUUUAAAGAUUAAACUUGUUCGAGGAAAAAAUGGUAAACACUGUUAGGGAUUGCCUGGCGUGCACAAAUUAAGGAAAGAAAGAAACUGAAAAUUUCAGCGCGGCUUUGGGAAUUUUUAGCUUUGCGAUUUAAAACCCACAGCGCCAUCUCCUGGUAAUGAGGAGAAUAUAGCGAUGGAUGACAAUACUGAAAUGCUGACUAUGAAAUACUCAAAUAUGAGAAACGCCUCAAAAAUUAUUUCAGUGAUAGGUUGAUUAUGAUUACAAAAUAUGAUCUGACAUGGACAUUUAUUAUCAUUAAAAGUUAUCAGACACAAUCCUGGAAGCUAAUUAUUUGUAAAUAGAAGUUUGUAUAUUUAUACAUACAUGUAUUUUAUAGAUUCAGACGCUUAUGCUGUGAAUUUACAAGAUAUGAUUCUAUAAUUUAUCAUAAAUACAUAAUUUUACAAAACAGUUCCCUGUUUUACUUUUUGUGAAUGAUUUUACCAUAUAUGGUAGAAAAAGAAUAAUAGGAUGUGGUGAUCUAUGGAGACAUAAAAUCUUCUAGAUCCUCAUUGUAUUUUACUAGUCAACAUUAAUAAAUACUUUAGCCCCAUUGUCUCAAUAACUUCUCACUUUAUCUAUGUCUUCUCAUCAUGCAAUCUUACAGAAUGUCUUACUGUCUUAAUGUUAAGACAUCAUGACAAAAAUGUGUUAACAUUAUUCAGACAUUCUGAUCCUGAAAUAUCAUCUGAAGUUAAAUUAUUUUCCAAAAGUUUAAUGCACAUAAUAGAAUCAUAAAUACUUAAUACUUUUCUAUUAAAAUGUUUCUGAAGUAUUCUUUCAAGCUUUUCUCCCUUUUAUAAAUAAGAUUGAAACACACUAAAAUUUAGAGAUGAUAUCCCUAUUAAAAACAUUUCUCCUCUAUGAUUGUAUACACAGGCCAGCUGCUUGAAAUAAAAAUAAAAGUAGAUAUGCUUUUUGUAGUGUACAAAAUAUUAUGAAUAUCCUUCAAAAUUGUAGAUCAAACAGACAAAUGUAAACUUCAGUUGAAAGAUUCAUUUUAUUUGAUUAAUUAAAGUGAAGAUCUAUUAAGCCAAA